GUCCCGCGUGGGCGCCCACGCAGGUCCGGCGCGCCGACCGCAAGUCCCCCGGCAGUGCCGCCCAACCCCGCGCUCGGAAGUGUGGCCUCAGAAGCCGGGGCGGCGCGGACACCUGCCGGGCUCCGGGGGAGUCUGGGCUGCCUCAGGCGUCGCGCGCCGUCCGCCGCUGGGUCCUGGGCGCCCACCCGGCUCUCCCCCGCGGGGGAGCGGCCCCUCUGCCCUCGACGGGCGGCGCGAGCUCCGGACCCGGUGCGCGCGCCAAGGCGGCCGCGGCCGCUGCUUGGGUGACAUGAGCGUGGCCCGGCGUCUCGGGGACUCGCGCUCCCUCGGUGUCCGCGGCUCCCGGGGGUAGAUGGCCGGGAGCCUGCACCCUGGAGCCCGGCCGCCGUCGGAGAGGCCUUGGGACAGCGCAGGGCCGGGGGUCCUGGGUUUAAAACCUCUCCAGGAGCGGAGGGAGGGCGCUUUGUGUGGGGGCUUCUGCCGCGGUUCUGAUGGCCGAGCGGUGUGACCUUUGGCAAGUCGCUCCCCUGACAAGCUCCUUUGCAGUCAGUGGCAAUGUCUACACCGCUGGGUUGUCGGAAAGAUCUAAUGCUGCGUUGCCACAGAGCCUGGACCGGGGCCUGACCCUCACCGGCCCCCACGGGGCCCUCCCAGCCCCGCAGCCCUCGGCUGUCCCCUCUUCUGUCAGUGAGCAAGCAGGCCACGCCCUGGGCACAAAGGCGGCAUUACCCUCAAAGGACCUCCCGGCGGGUCCCUUUUUCCUCUCUCAACCAGCUACCGGGCUGAGGGGCGGUGAGUUGGGGUUGAUCCAUGUUUAUGGCUCCUGGAGAGGCCGUUAUUUUGAGGUCACACCAGGGGACCUCUCAGUGCAGUUAACAAAUCUACAAACUACACACUCAGAGGGUUAAGUGAAGUGACAGGGAAGCACCGACUCAUAACUCUAAACCUUAGUGCCAGGCAGUGUUAAAUGUAGUUUCAUCGUUAUCCGUGGCAGAAGCCAGCAAGGUGUGGUGGCGUCCCUGAUUGAUAGAAAUGACAUUAGUUCUGCAUCCCAAGCCCCACGUUGAUGUACUAUUAGGUGUGUGGCUGGAGGGGUGGAUUCCACCAUUCGAAUGAAGGAAUCUUCACAAGGCAGGUUCGAGUUUACUGAAAGAAUGCUAGCACAUCUUUGGAGACCUUUUAAAUAUAUGCAUAUAUAUAUAUAAAAUGUUACAUAUAUACACAUAUACACACAUACAUAUACGCACAUGUAUAUCCAUAUAGAUAUUUAGUUUUUUUAACCACUCAAGGCCCUCCAAACAUCCUGUGAUUUCAGAUUUUGCCGUCGGGUAGCACUGACUUCGUUUGUCUCUGUAGUUCUUGACUCUCCCUGGCUGAUUGUCCAGGCUGAAGAAGGUGUUCCUCAUGUUUGCGUAGUGCCCCUGGCUCCUGCCACACUUCGCUGCUGUGCCCAGGUGGCCCAGCAAUUUGUCUUCAGCUAAAAGUGACUCUUAAACUACGCGAUAAAUUACAAAGUGCCUGGGUUUUGGGAUUCUAAAAUUAAAUGAGCAGAAUGGAGCUGAAAUUGAGCUGUGAGCUCACACUGCAAGAGAGAGGCAGAGAGGCACAGGUAACUCUCCCCGGAAAUUUCUAUCUGUGGGAAUAAAAAUGCCUAACCCUUGGCCAUGCCGCCCCUUUGAGACAACCUCUGUCAGGCUCACUGAGUUCUUAGUGCAGUCUGCUCUCCUGGUUUUGCGGAUGGGAGAGAAGAUUCGCCCCGAUGCACACUCCGUACCCAGGAUAUUCUGGGGAGUUAAUCGGGGUCUCCCCAGCUCUGUCUAGUGCAGCCAGCAUGAAUGCCACGCAGCCCGGUCACUCAGGCAUGGUGCUGGCAGUGGCACUGCGGUGACAUUCACUAACAGAGAUUAGCUGGUUGGGGAUAGGAGCUGUCUCAGAGGCUUGUGUGUGAUUACUCACGGAGGGCCUAUUACUCUUUAUUCCAAAACGAGCUUUUCUUUCCCCCCUCUAAGUGCACUGCUAAUGUGGAAAAGGCCUGGAGCAUUUGAGCCUCUACCCACUCAAUAAGAACUCUUUGAAAACCUUAUUUGCCUUUUUUUCAGCCAGGAGAAUUUGUGACUCAUAAAUAAGAUGUAGAUAUUAUUAGCUUUGACUUACAGAUGAGUAAAUGGGGGUGAAGUAAGGGAAGGAAGCUGUUUGUGUUCACAUGGUACGCAUAUGUCACCUCUGACAGUUCCAUCCCUGCUCAUUUGCUUCUGCCGUAUUCUCUGUUCUGAGGUCUCCUUUGUGAAACUCUUUCUCCAAGCCCUUAAUGGGCAAUUAGUGUUAUGUUCUGUACUUGCCUGAAUCGCAGCCCUGGUUUUCUCCCAGAUAGUCGCUGUGCUCAAGGUUCUUGCUUGUUUUACUUUCUUCCAUACAACUAAUAACUGGAUUCAGUUUAUUUCACAUGGCCCAGAGGUAAUUUAGACUGGUGGUUAUUCACCUUUCUUGUGUCAUGGCUCCCUUUCAGCACCUGAUAAAGGCUGUGGAUCCUCUCCAUUGUAAAAUAUGCAUCACCAGGGACAAGACAAGACAGCCUCUCUUUGUCCCUCUACUCAUCAGUCCAGGUAACACCACAGGAUUUCAAAGGGAAUAAAAAUGUGGAAGUGUCCAAUGUCAUUAUCGGCAGAUGACAUAACUACAUGGAUAAUCCAAAAGAGCCUGGAGAUUAACCCCUGGAGCUAAUAAGGGAGUUGAUCAGCAACAGCCACCUGCAUGGCAGCACAUCUGAGAAGACGAAAGAAACCAUUCUUCAUUCUUGCAUAAAAGCUGUUAGAUACGUUGAAAUAGGUCUUUUAAAAAGGUGAGACUUUUAUAGAGAAACAUAAAAUAUUUAGAAGAAGGACUGAGAAAAGAAAGUUUAGGCUGGGCAUGGUGGCUCAUCCCAGCACUUUGGGAGGCUGAGGCAGGCGGAUCACCUGAGGUCAGGAGUUCGAGACCAGCCAGACCAACAUGGAGAAACCCUGUCUCUACUAAAAAUACAAAAAUUAGCUGGGCUUGGUGACACAUGCCGGUAAUCCCAGCUACUUGGGAGGUUGAGGCAGGAAAAUAGCUUGAACCUGGGAGGCGGAGGUUGCAGUGAACCGAGACCGCACCAUUGCACUCCAGCCUGGGCGACAAGAGUGAAACUCCGUCUCAAAAAAAAAAAAAAAAAAAAAAAUUUAAAUAAAUGGAGAGAUGCGUUGUGUUCAUGCAUGGGAGGGCUGGCUCUCAUAGUUGCCCCAAUUUAAUCUGCAAAUUCAAUGUAAUCUAGUUUAAGCUGUGACAAGAUUUAAUGUGGAAUAUGAAAUCACACAAAUGAAUUAUAAAAUUCAUAUGGAAGAGUAAGGUCCAGGAAUACCUCAGACAACUCUGGGAAAGAAGAGGAGGAGGGGAGUUGUGGUAACGACAGUCCAGCAGUAGAGUCAACUCAAACCCAAGCAUGUGUGGGAACUUGUAUGUGUGAGCUGAAGAGUUACAAAUAGAUGGGGAAGGAUGGGCUAUUUACUAAAUGGUGCUGGGAGAACAGGCUCUCCCCAUGGAAAAACAAUUAGAUCCUCACAUUACACAACAGUACAUUCCAGAUGGGAUUAAAGACUGUAUAUAAAACUUUAGAAAGAGCUGCAGUGGAAUACCUUUGUCACACCGGGAAAGGAGUCCCUACACAAGUUAUGAAAAUAAAUUUCAAAAUGAAGAGACUGAUACAUUAAGAUAAAAAUUCUAUGUAAACAAAGGCAUCCUAACAGAGUUAAAAAGCAAGAAUAGACCAGGAAAGUAUUUACAAUAUAUAACAAAUACAUUAGUACACAGAUUAUUUUGAAAACUAUAAAUCACUAAGAAAAAAAGAUACACGCCAGGUAGAAAAAUGGGGAAGUUUAUGAAUGGAGAAGUCAAUGAAGAGAAAUCCAAAUGACCAGUAAACAUAAGAAAUGAUGCCCAGCUUCACUCAAGUUCGCUGGGGGUUAUUGGAGCACUGCAAUUUAGGCAACGAUGAGAUACCAUUUCACACCUAUUGGAUUUCCCGACACGGAAGAGUGUUAGCAUCACGUGCUGGCAAGGAUAUAGAGCAAUGGGAACUUUCAGAUGCUGCUGGUGGAGAUUGGUAUCGUUUGGAGAGCAAUUUGGCGAUACACGGUGAGGCUGGACUUGCUAGUCCACAGCCAGACAUAUCCUGGAAGAACUCUCCCACGUGUGCACAAAGAGACUUGUAUAAGAAUGUCCAUGCAGGCGUUUUUUUAAAUGAAGGAAAACCCACCUUCCCUGAAGUAGAAUAGAGAACUAAAUCAAAAUAGUCACACCAUGCAAGACUCUACAGUGGUUAGAAAUGAAUAAACCAGAUCUAUAUCUACACAGAUACAUCUCUCAAAUAGUGUUGAGAGAGAAAAAAGGCAAAUUGUAGGUGUCCAAUGUGAUCAUAUUCAUGUAAACGUUAAGAAACACACAAAGCAGGCCGGGCGUGGUGGCUCACGCCUGUAAUCCCAGCACUUUGGGAGGCAGAGGCGGGUGGAUCAUCUGAGGUCAGGAGUUCGAGACCAGCCUGGCCAACAUGGUGAAACCCUGUCUCUACUAAAAAAAUAUGAAAAUUAGCUGGGCGUGGUGGUGCACGCCUGUAAUGCCAGCUACUCAGGAGGCUGAGGCAGGAGAAUGGCUUGAACCUGGGAGGUGGAGGUUGCAGUGAGCUGAGAUGAACAGGACUGCACUCCAGUCUGGCCGACGAGUAGAGUGAAACUCUGUCUCAAAACAAAAACAAAAACAAGCAAAAACAAAGCACAAAGCAAUACUGUAUUAAUUAUGGAUGCUUAUAGAUGUAGUAAAAGUAUAAAAGUGUGGGCUGUAAGGAUCUGCAUCAAAUUCUAGUUAGCAAUGACCUCCAAGAAGGGAGGGAGGGGAGAGGAACUUCAAACUUUAUCUGCAGUGUACUGCUUUACAACACACGCUUAUGUGUGUGGGUGUGUGUAUGUAUAAACAUACGUGGAUUAUAUACAAAAUUGUGCCUAGACAUUUUGUACUUUUUUUCUUUGUAUCAGGGUAUAUUACAUGUGGUGAUGUGUACAAGUGUGUAUAUAUACACACGUAUAAUAUAUAAACACACGUAUAUUGACGCAUAUACCUAUAUACAUAGACAUAUACACAGAUACACAUAAAACAUUGAAGAGAGAAAAAAGAAAAGGGAGAUGCACAUGGUACACCUACCGCAUGGUGCUUCUGGACCAUCUGAAGCCCACCGCUGGAGGCAGGUGCCUGCAGGCCCAUGUUAAGAAGUCCCUACUUUAGAUGUCCAGACUGGGCCGAUCCACUUGUCAAGGAAAUGGUGACAGAGAAACAGAAUGUCUGGCUGCAGGUCGCAUGGGCGUUUGGACAGAGCUGGACACGGAGCCCAGGAACCCUUCCCUUCUCCCCUGCUUCUUUCUCCUUCCAGUCACCCUCGCUCUAACCUGUGUGCAUUGUCACCUUUGACAUUGUGACUCAGAAAAGACAAGUUGCUUGUGUGGAGAGGAUGGCAGCAAGGUAUUCUCCACAUACCAAAUCACAACAGCUCAGCGUCUGCUGCUCUUGGAAAUGAUGUUUAUCUUAAGGGUGGUUCUUGGAUGCCAUGCUUUCCCUUGGGUUUUUGCUUUGCCUGGGGUAUUGAGCUAAUUUGUUGCUUCUGAGUCUGAACAUAAAAAGGCAGGCUGGCUGCCAGGGCCCUAAAAGAUCUAAGAGCCUUAAAUGAUCUUGAACUUGCCUUAAAUAGUUUUACUUAAAAUAGCUACUGAGCAGGACAUACCUGGCCCAGAAUUUCAGGUGAGCCUGCACGAUUCAUUUGUCAGCAGAGGAAAAUUGUCAUGCUGCAGACAACUUGUUCUUGCAAUGAAAAACAAGCCGAAGCCUUAACCAGGUGUUAAAAUGAUGGGCCAGAACUUGUUCCAGCCACAGCGUCAGGGGUUUGGUAGGGACAAGGGGAGACCCGGAAGAGCAGUCACCUGUGACCUAGUUCUCUGGGAUUGGUUUUCGGUCUAAGGCUGUCUUGGUUUUAUGCUCUGAGCCAAGCUGGACUGGCUGUGCGCGGCUGGCCUGCGAGAGGUUCUGGGUGUGAACUGAGGGACAGAGGCAAGAUGAGGGUUGUGAAGCUCAUUGUCUUAACCCUCCUAUCUGACGUCUUCACCCGGAUGGUGAUGCCUUUAAGUGGGCAGGAGUUUAAUUGACCGGACUGCCCUCCUGAGUCAUUGGAGCUGGUGCGGGGAGUGGUGAUCAAAGCCGAGCCAGCUGCCAUCUCUGGAGCCAGAAAAGCUCCAGAAGGCAGCAUCCAGGGCAGACUCAGAAUCAGGACUGAGCAGGUGCAGGGGCAGACUCAGAAUCAGGAGCAGACUCAGAAUCAGGACUGAGCAGGUGGCUCAGCUGACUGGACCAUUAGAAAGGCUUGAGUUUCUCUGGGCGGAAACCAGGGAAGCAAAUGAGAAACACGGAGCUGUCGAUGGGCUGGGGGAGGCUGGGACACCGCCUGAUACUCCUGCCGGCUUUGAGCUUUGGGUGGUGACAGGGACACUCAGGGCUGUCCAGACCCUGUUCUCCAGUGUCCGCCAACUGCAUGCCGGCUGGGAACGUCCUGAGCUUUUUUGGAUCUCUGAGCCUCUACACAGAUUGUGGCAUCUAGAAAGUAGUUCCUCUGAUCUUCUGCAGCUCAGCCAGGCUGCCGACACCUCUCCUCCUCCUUUCACCCUGCCCUGGGAGGGCUUCCGGGUUGUACUUGCCCUGGGUGGCUGGCCUCCUCCUGGCUCCUGGGACUGGGUCUUGGCCUUGCCACCGACCAGAAGCCCUGGUCUUGCUCCCACCAGCUGAUGUUUCUCCUGACUAUUGCUCCGAAGGCCCUCACCAGCCCUGCAGGGAGGUGUCACCAGGCCUGGUUAAUGGUGAUGAGGCCUUAGACCCAGGUACCUUCUGACAAACCAGUGACUGACAGGCCAGGGCCGGACCCCACACCCUCUGACUCACCUUCUACUGCUGUCACCUCGUACCUGCUUCCCAGACAAAGGUAAAUCAUCAGACAGAAAAGCCUUUCGGCUUCUGCCAGAAUGAACAGACAAGAGGCAUAGCAACCUCCGGAGACCCCACCAGCCGCCGUUUCUCCCUCUGUCCACCGGGUGCGUGCACAUGCGUGUGCGUGAACGCGCACAGACUCAAAGGGCUGCACACCAGCAUGGCUCUGUCUCGGGGAAUCUGUACUGGCUCCUGCUCAUCAGCAUUGGAACCACUCACACCUCUCUCUAUUGGAGGGAAAAAGAAAAGCCCUCCAGUCCUUCUAGGAAGCCACUCAAACUACACAUUUGAGUCACUCACAUUUCAGUCACUCAAGCUGCACAUUUAUCAGCUGGACUAAUCAUCUUUUGCUGAAACCUCCUCCUCGUGUGGGUCCCUGUCUACAAGAAGAGACCCCUGUCUACCUUAGUGGCAGAGCUGGAGGCCUAGAGGUCACCAUCGCCUCCUCCUGCUCCCGUGCUCCCCCAAGCCUGUCUCACUGUCUCCUGAAUGGCUCUCAGGCUCCCUGCAUUGCCCCUGCCACCGCCCAGCACAGGCUGUGGCCUCUGUGGCCUCUACCUGCCUCAGGGCCUCCUCCUGCCCCACCCCACCGCCUCGAGCCCUGGCUGUAGCUGCAGCUCUGCCCAUCCCCCAUCUUCAUGCUUUUGCUUCCUUUCAGGCUUUGCUUCUGUUGUUCUUCCUGCCCAGAACGGCUUUACCUGUCACCAGGUUCGCCCCUCAGCCUUCCCACCCGUCACCAGGUUCGCCCCUCAGCCUUCCCACCCGUCACCAGAUUCGCCCCUCAGCCUUCCAAGUUCUGCUGCACUGUCAGUUCCAUCAGCCGACUCACCCCGAUUUCCCCAGCCCGCCGGAUGUACCCUUCGUCUGGGCCCCCAGGCCCCCUGCCACCUGGACGUUGCCUGCUGGCUUGCCUGUUUCUGACACUGGGCUCUGGGCUUCCUGGGUGAGUCAGCCCAAAGUUAGGCCUCUGGCUGCUCUCUAAGGUUAGUUCCGAUUCUGCCACCUCUGUGGUGGCCGGCAGACGUGCGUUCAUUUAUUCAGCGAGUAUUGCUGUGUGCUCUCACUGGCCUGGGCACUUAGAGAUAAGAAAAUGUGGCCCCUGCCUUGCAAGAGUCUUAAGAGACUCUUGGUUAUGAGUCUUUGUGAGGGACCAAGGCCAGGCACCUGCGCUUUGUUUAAGUGUCAUUUAUUGAACCACCCCCACCAUCGCUUUCUCAUCCCAAUCGUUUGCUUUUUGGAGUCACUCGAUAGGCCCUGCCACGUACGUACUUGUACAUGAGGACACCCUCUUUGUGAUGCUGUAGUUUGCCUCUUGGCCAGGUCAGCUCCACACUGAUCUGAGAGCCCUGUGUCCCCUGAAGGCCCCACUAGUGCCCUGGAGGCCCCACUGGUGCCCUGGAGCUCACUGUGGAUGCUUCACACCCUGCGGGUCCCAUCAUCCCAUCAAGCUGUGGUUUUUCCUGAUGUCCUUGUGCCUCUGCCCUUUGAGCAUCUGGAGGACCCAGCAGCAGGCGCAAGGCCCCCUGUCUAGUCCUGCAAGGAAGGGGGAUGAAUAGCCAUCAGCUGUCAGGAGCCUCACGCUCCAUGGGAUGGGAUCAGCAGCCUAGGGUUCCCAUGGCAACCAGCCCAUCAAUGCCCUCAGUGUCAAGACAGGGGCACCGUGGAAAGGAAGAAAGUCUCAUUGUCUUGCCUUGGCUGCUUGGGCAUAAACAAGCUGCGCUCCACAGGGCCCCGCAGCCACGCCCGACCUGUGGCUCUGCCCAGCCGCACAUGGACCCAUUUACUGAAUUGGGCUGGGAAGAGGCUGUCACUGUUAGUUCUCUAAUCUUCCUCGGGGGCUCUUGUAUUUCUGCCACCGGCCAGCAUCCAUCACUUCUAGAGUCCUUGUUGGGAAAAUCCAUCUUCUCAGUGAGAGUGGGCAGAAACAGCCCAAAUGGAGCAGACUACCGAAGCUCUGAGUGAUCAGCCAGACCGCCCUGGGGGGAAUCCAUCAGUGGGUAAUGGCAUCACUCACGUUCCUGCAAGGAACCUGGACUUCCAGACUUUCCCGCUUUGGUUUCAAACACCCUGAUGACAACUCUCAGACAUAUCUCCUGUGAUCAUUUAAGCAGAUCACCUUGAGAUGACCACUGCUGGGCUUGCCACAGGCGGACAGUCUAAGAAGGUCCUGUCCCCCUUCCUGGACUGUCCCCCUGGGAGGACCCCAGCAGUGGUCACUUACAAGAGCUUCCUUCUUGCCUUCAAAAGGCCCAAGUUCACCUCCCUGAUCAUUGCCGGACUCUUCCCUGGGUGGAGAUCUGGGAAGGUGGUGGAGGGGAAGGGAGGGGCUGCCUCGUGUUGGAUAAGGGCCCUCCCACCAGAGGUCAGGCCUGCUGUUCCCUGUCUAGUAGAAGGCUGCAUGGAGGUGCUCCUGUGCCCCACACCGUUCUGCUCACCUAUCUUGUACCCCGUCCUCCAGAUGGGAAACCAGAUGUCUCUCUGGAUUCCUCCCACCAGCCUCUGCAUGCACCGACCACAGCCCUGUCCGACCAGCCUCUGGGUCUUUCUCCCCUGCCACCCAGCCCAUGGCCACAGCCGAGGCCGGGCCUGCUCACUCAUACUCUCACUGGUGGUGAGUGUCCUGGUGACUGCCUCACUGGCUUCCCUGCCUCCCUUCCAGGCCAUUUCCCACACGGCCAUCCGUAGGAUUCUUCAGAGCCCCACUGCUCUGUGCUCACCCAGAACCCUUCACUUUUACCACACGCAUCUUCAUGAAGUCCGGGCCUUUGACAUUCAGGACACUUUCCAUAUGCUUUUUCUUUCUUCUGCACCUAUCUGUUGCUGUCGUUUUAACCUGGGGGCCCCUUCCUUGUGUGGUCUACCCGGGCCCUGCCCUUCUUUGGCAUUAGCCAAAGUGCUGCUUCCUGACCUGCCUGCAGCCCUGUCCUCUCCGAGCUCCACGGAGGGGCUCGGCCAUGGCGUGCGGGGUGUCUCUCUCCCCGCUAGACCCUCUGGACCACAGCGUCUCAUAGUCUGCGUCUUUACGUGACUCAUUUUGCUUCCUGAGGCCCUAGUGCAGUUCCUGGCACUGAGAAGGUUUAGUGAAUGAGAAAUUGUUAGAAUUUUUUAUAUCAGGACCUGUGAUGUCCUGAUUCCAUUCACCAAAGGCAAAUCAUCCUUAAGCGUGAGUAUGGAGAAAAUGCUGACCUUGUUAUCUUCACUUCUGCUGAGCUCUAGCAGGUUUGUGAGCAGCAAAUAUUUGUGAUGUUUCUGUAUAGUCAAAUAUCGCUUAUGCUUUCCACCCUUUGACAUCUCUUGGUACCUUGCUUUUGGGUUCUGUGUUUCCUGGGACUGAGUCUUGCUGAGUGAUUCCAGUGUCACCUGCAGGGACUCUGCUCUCAAGGCCAAGGCAGAUGUUCAGUCAUCUGUGCCACGUGGCUACUCCGAGGCAGAACCGGCAAGUCUGGACACACCUAGCAUCCUAGCCUGGUGUUCUCUGAAGCUCAGAACGAGCAUCUUGCUCCUUGGUGGGCAGAAGAACAAGAGGAAAGGAAGCCAGAAAAAGAGGACCGGGGAAGCCACAGAAGAGGGAGGGAGGGAAAGUGGGAAGGAGGACUGAGGACAGGAGGCAUGGGUGUGUCCUGCGGCCUUGGUGGAGCCUGUCCUGUGGAAGGUUUAUUUUCUGUAAAGAAGCAGUCUGGCUCGUGCCUGUACUCAGCCUCUCUGUCCCCACACGUGACUGUCCUUAGAAUAGCAACUGGGUCCUCGGAUUCCAGUACCCCACCAUGACUGCCGCCAGCCACUCCUAUGUCAGUCUUGGCUGUCUGCCAGGCACUGCUGAUGAUUGCCCCCAGAACCGUACUAUUAAUCCCAUUACACAGAUGAGCAAACUGAGACCCACAGAGGCUGAGUAACCUGCUAUAGUAGUAAGGGUCAGAGCAAGGCUUUCAACCUGGGCAACUUGCAUUCCAGGCCUUCCUCAUAGACAGAGUCUGUGUCUAUUAGGAAAGGCUACAAGGAGCAGGUGGCAUGUGAGCCGCCACGGAGCUUGGCUUGGGGCUUUCUAAGUGGCUAGGGCAGAGGGGUGCAGUCCAGGCAGAUGGAGGGUUGGGGCAGAAGGGACCUGUGAAGAAGUCCUCCUGUACUAUGGGAUCCUCCCCUCCUUAUCAGGGCUCUGGCCUGGAGCUCAGUUCAAAGGCUUAUCUAUGCAGGAAUGAAGGCAACAUUCUUGAUGUAGAGUCUAAGAGUCUGAAGGUCAGGGAACCUUUCUUGGAUACCCUCCUUUCUGCCUACCAGAACCCUGUGUUUCCUGCCUGCUGGGAGGCAAGUGGAACACAGUAGAACCAGAUCCCAAGAGGAGAGAAGAGGCUGGAGGGGGACCCACAGUUGCAUAGAGGGUAGCAUGGCCUGGUUAUAAGACUGUUUACACUACUUGAUUCCUCUCAGUAUAAUACAGAAAGGAUAUGUGGAUACAGAAUAUUUUUGCAAUACAGAAAAGAACAAGAAAACCAUAAAAAUCACCCAUAGUCCCACCACCCCAAAAUAAUCACUGUUGACACUUUGGGCCAUGACUUUUUGUUUUGUGAUUCUGUGUCUGAGUGUGUGCGUGCACACUCAUAUGCAGGUUGAAUAUCCUGUAUCUGAGAUGCUUGGGAAAAGAAAUGUUUUGGAGUUCCAAUUAUUUUAGAUUUUGAAAUAUUUGUGUUAUGUUCACUUGUUGAGCAUCUCUAACCUGAAAAUCUGAAAUUGGAAAUGCUUUGAGUGUCCUGUUGGAUUUUGGAGUAUUUUAGAUUUUCAGGUUAGGGAUAUUCAACCUGUGUAGGUAUGCAUGCACACACACACAGACACACAGACACACACACACACGCACACACAUAUAUUCACCAAUGUCUUAUACAAAUAGGAUUGUCUACUUUUGCAACUUGUACCUCCCACGUCAAUAAGUCUUCUAUGGCGUAACUUGUAAUGGCUGCUCAGUGUACCUUGGCGUAGCUGGCCCAUCAUUUGUGUCAUUCUUUCCUGACGUUUAGGUCAGUGAGUUCUUUAUCACUGCGUGGGGAGGUGGAUAGUGCUGCAGCUGCUGUGGAAGGUCAGGACCGUGCAGGGAGGUGGAAGAGGCUCUGCCACUGCGCUGCUUCCCCGCCCCACAUGCCCUGGGUCCCUGGUUAUGGCGUCUCAUCCCACCUACCUGCAUCUCCCGUCCGGCAUCACCAGCCUUGCAGAGGGUCCACACUUGGUAACAUCUGUUCAGUUCAACUCAUUAGGAUUUUAUCGAGCAUUUUUAUUUAAAAAAUUAUACAUUGCAUAUAAAUUUAUAAAUUUAGAGUAUUAUAUAAAUGCUCCCCCAUUGUAAAGAAUUCACACAGUGCAGGUGUACAAAGCAAAAUCCAAAAUCUCCUUCCUCCCCUCAUCCGAUCCCUGAUUUACUCCUUCCCUGAGAUGUCACCACUGUUCACACAUUAGUAUAUGUGUCCUGUUUCUGUGCCUUAACAGACAGAUACGUGCGCAUAUACACACAAAAAGAAUUUUUGUUGUUUUUUUUUUUUUUAAUAUAAAUGGAAUCACACUAAACAUGUUUUUUUUUUUGGACCUACCUAGGUUUUCUUCACUAACAGUGGGACGUCUUGGGAAUCUUCCCAUGCUCGUACAUAGAGACCUACCUCAUUCUUUUUAAAUAGUUUUAUGGCAUUUUAGAGAUGCAACAUGUUUUGUUAUACCACACCUGUGAAUGUUCCUUUGAUUUGCCUCCAGUUUUUUUCUGUUAUAAGCAGUGUUGCAGUGGUUAUCCUUAUUCAUGACUCUGCACUUGUGAGAAUUUCUGUAGGAUCCAUAAGAACAAAACAAAUACUAGUUAUAAUAAUAAAUGGUGAUUGCUGGCCCUUACUGUGUACCAAGUAACUUUUCAUGUGCUUUCCUUGUAUUGACUCAUUUAAUCUUAGAAACUCUAUGGGGUAGGUGUUAUUAUUACCCUCAUUUUACAGAUGUGGAAACAAAAGCACAGAGAGGUUAAGUAACUUUUUCCCAGUUACACAACUUGUAGGUGCCAGAGCCAAGAUUUGAACCCGAAUAGUCUGACUCCAGAGAGGGGACCUGCUGAGUCAAUGUAUGUGUGCAAGUUACAUUGUGUUAGAUGUUGGCCAUGGCUCUCCCAACAGAUAGUGCCAGUUGACACUGCCCCCAGAAGUGUGUGUGGGCCCCACCGAUUUUGUGUAGUGAUGACCAAUUGUCAUAUUUGCCAGUUCUUAUAGGUGACAAAUGAGAUCUGGUGGUUGUUUUAAUAUGCUUCUUUUCCCUCAUUGUUAUUCAAGUUAAAUGUUGCUUGGCCAGCACAGUGGCUCACACUUGUAGUCCCAGCACUUUGGGAGGCUGAGGCUGGAGGAUCAUUUCAGCCCAGGAGUUCGAGACCAGCCUGGGCAAGAUGGCAAGUUCCUGACUCUACAAAAAAAAAAAAAAAAAAAUUAGCCAAGUGUGGUGGUGUACGCCUGUGGUCCCAGCUACUGGGGAGGAUGAGGUGGGAGAAUUCCUUGAGCCCAGGAGGUUGAGGAGUCAGUGAGCCAAGACCACAUCACCGCACUCCAGCCUGGACGACAGAGCGAGACCCUGUCUCAAAAUAAAUGAGUAAAUAAAGUUAAGUGUCUCUUUAUUUAUUAGGCAUUUUAAUCCUUCUCUGAAUUGCUUAUUUAUAUUCUUUGCCCAUUUUUUCAGUGGGGCUGUUUGUCUUUUAAUGAUUGCUUUCUCUGUGUUGUAGAUAUUCAUCCCUUGUUUUUAAGUACGUUGCUUUUCAUUGAACACUGUUCAGAGUGUUUGUUGGCUUUGCCUGUUGUUGUUUGAAGUAAAAUCUGCAGCACCAUUUGUUUGCCAGGCUUUGGGCUCGUCACUCAGUGUAAUUCAGAGAUGAGUAAGACAAAGUCCCCACCUAAAAUAGACAGCACGUAACUCUUGCGAGAGGAGUAGUGAACGGAAUAUAGGGGCGGAGUCCAAAUGUUUUAGGAUAAGUGAGGAGAAUGGGGCAGCCUCUCAACUGGGGAUUCAGGGAAGCCUUUGUGACCAGUGGCGCUAGGGCCAGACCUGGAGGGGUCCAUAGAAUGUUCACAGAGGAAUGGGAAGUGGGGGUGUGUUUGGGCAGAUGGAUCGUGAGUGCUUUAAUCUGCAUCCCAUCCGAAAACAACUCACCUUCAAUGACCCACUGGAAAAGAGUCUCAUGAAGAGGCUACUUACAGGGUGUGCAUGGGGACAAGGGAACCAACAGAGGGUGUUGAGGUACCCGGGGACUGGGUAGGCAGUGGUGGGGAGCUGCUGCAGGGAUGGAGGCAAAACAGUGUUAGCAGAUCCUGUGGGAGCUGGAGCUGAGUAGGGUGCAGCCUCCUUCUGGUGCCUCCAUUGGCCUGGGCAGUAUUGCCUGGAGGGCUUAGUCUUCUGCAGCACUGAGCAGGGCAGAGAAUGGUGGAGAGUGGGUCAGAGGUGUCAGGGGAGGUGGAGGGAGAAAAAUCAGCUCAGUAAGGAUAAAAGCAGAGAUAGAAGUUCCAGAUGUGUGAAGGCCUCAGCAAUCCUCGAUGCCAUUAGAGGGUAGGGGGGUUCAUUUGCUGCUGGUUUUACUUAGCAAACAUUUAUUGGAUGCUGGCUCAAAGCCUGGCCCCGGACGAGGUGCUAAGUUAUAAAGAUGGGUCAGGCAGGCUGCGCACCCCAGUGAUCACCGCCGUGGCGCCAGUUUUAGCUUUCCACGUGUCCUCUCCGAGGGUCACAGCAGAGGCCUGUGGUUUUAUGUCUGUUAGACCCCAUGUACCUGGAUCUGUGCCUCCUUGUCCCAGUUGGAGUUUAUUUAGGUGUGUCUGUCUGAGGACAGAUUUUAACAUGGAAAAAUAAGUCCAUUUUUGGCCGCCAUUGAAUUCAGUCUAACAUACAUCUUGAUCUUCUGCUGUUUUUUUCCAACUUAAACAAACAAACAGAAAUCCCAAUUUGUGUUCCUCUUGAUAAAGCCCAAUUUCUAUAGAAAGAAAAGAAACCUUAUUGCUGUCCUAUCAAAGUAACCAUUUAUGACUGAGCUCAUUAACAGUCUUAUACACGGUUCUGUUUCUCAUUUGCAGGAAUAUGAUGCCGUUAGCCAAGAACAAGAAGUUAGAUUUGUUUCAGAGGCUUAGACAACUUUAUGUAUCAUGACUUUGAUAAUCUAAGACCCUCACAACCAUUCAUUCAUUCAUUCAUUCAUUAUUUAUUUAUUUAUUUACUUAUUUAUUUGAGACAUGAGUCUCACUCUGUCACUCAGGGUGGAGUGCAAUGGUGCGAUCUCAGCUUACCGCAACCUCUGCCUCCCAGGUUCAAGGAAUUCUGCCUCAGCCUCUCUAUUAGCUAGGAUUACAGGCGCACGCCACCACCUCCAGCUAAUUUUUAUAUUUUUAAUAGAGAUGGGGUUUCACCAUGUUGGCCAGGCUGGUCUUGAACUCCUGACCUCAGGUGAUCCACCCACCUCGGCCUACAACCAUUCAUUUUAGCACAAGAUGCAAAAGCCUGUCUGUGGGAAUAGAUGCUUUCUCUUCCCCAUGGAGUUCUGUGAACUCAUUAGUACUUUCUAGGAUUUUUGUUUGCUUGCCUGCUUUUUCAAGGAAUUUGCUAUUCUACCUUGUUCUGAUAUUUGGUCAAAUCAGAAAACGUUAGAAAACCAAAUUGAUUCUUUCUUACACUAAAUAAUCUUAAAAUCCAAAUGAAGGCUAGGCAUGGUGGCUUAUGCUUGUAAUCCCAACACUUUGGGAGGCCGAGGUGGGAGGAUCCUCUGAGCCCAGAAGUUCGAGGCUGUAGUGAGCUAUGAUCAUGCCACUGUACUCCAGCCUGGAUGACAGAGUGAGACACUGUCUCUACAAAAAAUAAAAAAAUUAGCCAGUCAUGGUGGCAUGUGCCUAUAGUCCCAGCUACUCAGGAGGCUGAGGCCAGAGGAUUGCUUGAGCCUGGGAGGUCAGGGCUAUGCAGUGAGCUAUGAUCAUGCCACUGCACUCCAGCCUGGGUGACAGAGCGAGACUCUGUCUCUAGAAAAGAAAAGAAAACAAAACAAAAACCAAUCCAAAUGAAACCUCAGAGGUAGGUAUGGACACAUUAGCUCUGGGAGACUGUCAAUACAAGGCUCACAUUGAGGGACCAGAACUAACAGACCCACACUAUCACAAGCCAGGUCUUAACAGCCUUCCUUUUCCAACCAGGGAAGGGCAGCUCUCAAACCUAACCAGAGGAUCUUUCCACUUUCUCUUUUGAUUGUUACUCAUAAAGAGCCCUGGAUGUAUUUUCUAUUUUCUUCUGUCAAAAGUUCAAUGGCUACAGAGAACUAUAGAAAAUCCUGUCUUAACCCAAUUUAUUUUCUUAUUCCAAGUUGGUUCUACUUUCCAGCAAUUGGUUCCUUUCCUGGAGGUAGUUGCUUUGUGCUUGGUGUGUGCUGAUGGCUGUGCCAGCCUGGGCAUCUCAUCAUGCCAGGGAGCUGCUCAGCCUCCUCCCUGGUCUCUCCUGAAAACUGACCUCCUCAGUGGAGUCUCAGUGACCAGGCGCCACCAUUGAGAGAUCCUUUUGUCUCUCCAAGGUUGAGGGAACCUGUUUGUGCACUUGCCACUGUCAUUCUCCCCACAGCGUCAGUUUUGUUUGAAUCGUGCUGUCAGGUUGCAUGAAUUAGAUUGCAAGUCUCGAGCUUGGGCCAUGUUUCUGCAUGCACCGUGGGUGUGAAACUGAUGCCUGGCAGAUUGUCCCAUCGUUAGAAACACUGGACAGAGCCGGAAGGGAGCAGCCAUGCUGCCCAACCCGUUUUCAAUGCCAUGACUUUGUCCUGAGGCCUCUUCAGGGAGCUGUGUUAACGUUGAGCCCAGUUUGAUUUCUGCGUCGGCCCCUUCAUAGCAGAAGACGACCUGCUGACUGCUGUGGCCAGGCCACCUGGCCGUGGGGCUUUGAGGAGAGACUCAAGCCAACAAGUGCCGUCAGUCAGAGCAUGUCUCUGGUCUGCCUGUGUCCCCUUGCUGGGUUCUCAGCAAUCUGGGGCGAUGCCUCCGUUCGAUUUUUUUUUCCUCAGAGGAUUAUGGAGUUUUCUGGGUCAUUUAGCUUUUUUUUAUCACAAUUUCGUGUUUCUUAGGUCCAUCCAUAGGAGAAUGGAAAAACAAAUGUGAUACAUUCAUUCAGUGAGCACUCUUUUAUUCAGCAAUAGAAAGGAACAGACAACCAGCAUGCAUAACAACGUGCAUGUGUCUCAUAGACAGGCCAAGUGAAAGAAACCUUACAUGAGGGUGCCUGACUCCAUUCAGAGGAGGUUCUAGAACUGGCAAAACCAAAUGUGGGGGCAUGAAAGCUGGAGGUUGACCGGGAAGGCACAUGCGAGACUUUCUGGAGUGAUGGCUGUCUUCUGAAUCUCAGUAGGGGUUUGAGUUAUACAAGUGUGUACAUUUAUCCAAACUCAACAAAUGUGUAAUUUACUUUUGCUUGUUUCAUCAUAUCUAAAUUUUAUCUCAAAAGAAAUAAAUCUAUAAGCAAAUAAUGAUGUGUAUGUUGAAGUCUUUAGGGAGAUGUAUGUUGUGUACUGAUACUGCAGUUUACUUUGGAAUGCACCAAAAAUAAGAUGUGUUGACAAAUGGAUAGAAGGAUGGAUGGAUGGAGAGAAGUUUGAUCAAGUGAUUUUAGUGAAUAUGUUAAUGGUAGAAUCAAGGUAAUGGGCAUAUGGAUGUCUGCCAUACAAUUCAUUCAACAUUGGUGCAUGUUUGAAAAAUUUCAUAGCAAGAUGUUGGGAGAAAGGUAUUUUUGUGGACGUGGGAGAGACCCCAUGUUGUCUUUGAAGACAUAAUCAUAAAUUUAUGUUUAGAGAUGAGGAUUAGAAGCCUUUCUAGGGAUUUAGUAGGGCAAAUGAUGUCAUCAAAGAAAUCUCCUGGAAUCUGGGUUCAGGGGCAUUUGCUUUUGUAGAGGAUGUUCUGGGGCUACACUGGCAUCUGAAAGGAUUACUGUGGCUCUCUGAGCCACUAACUUGCUAGGCUUUCCCCAGGCAGAGUUUCAGCCCCAGGGAGAAGCUUCCCAGUAAAUGUAAAUGAGCAGAGUCCGUGGUUUAAGGACCUUCCUGCGGAGGAGAGAGAAGGAGGAGAGAUAAGCCGCAGACACCCCUGGCACGGCAAGGUAGGCUGGGUUGCUUGCCUGCUAAUUAUCUUCUCGGUCUUGCUCCGCAGUGUUUCUCUAGUUUCAGAAUUUGAAUUGCUGACUUUGUGUAGAAUUUUCAGCCUCUCGAGUUGUUGAAUUGAAGGGCAGCACCACAGCCAUUCCCUACAGAGUCCUAACGGACAGGCGUCCUAUGUCGGAAUCCUGAUCCUGUGUAACCCCGGGGAUGUACCAGGGCAAAUGCAGCAAAGACACAGCGGUCAGACUCCUUGUGGGAGAACCCCGGCCUAGGAGAAGCUGCUGGUAAAUUUAGGGCACGUUGGAGAAGUGGGGGUGGGGAGAGAAGAGAAGAAUGAAAGCAUUAUUCUAAGGAGCUACUUUUAUUUAUAGAUUCUCCUAAUUCUAUUAAAAUGAAUGCCGGAGGGAUGUAAAACUUGGAACACAUAACACAUAAUAGAAAUGAAAGGACAUUAAACUAAAAUAGGGAAAAAUGGUAAAAUGAGAAGAGAAUCUUAGUACCAAGAGGAAGAUGUGACAUUUUUCUGAAAUAAAAUAAUCUUACAGCACAGUGUAUGGGGAAAGUGAAUUAAAUAAAGUAAGGACUUGGUUAGCAGAAAACUUGGAAGGAAACAAAAUAUUUCAUAAUGAAAAGGAGAAAGUGUUAAGCUGACUCAAGGGGAAAACACAUACAGAUAUUACACUAAUUACAUUAUAAAGACAGAUAAAUAAGAUGUCAUUGUUGUAAAAGGAAAUAAAACUAAUUAAAUGUUUAAUGUGCUUUAAGAGACAUUGGUGAAAUAAAAUAUAUUAACUAUGGUAAAAUAUGUGAACAGGCAUAAUUCGCCUGCCUUGUUCUGGCAGCCAGCACAGUACCUCACCUCCUGUGUACAAAACAAGGGACGUUUGAUCCCUGAGUUGGAAUGGUUCAGCUCUUUCUUCAAAAAAAAUGGCAGUUAGAAGCACCUCCAACAACUGAAUGUUUGCAAUAAUGCCAGUCCCGAAGUGAGCACUCAGCGCGUGUUGUUGCCAGUCAUAUUGAUAUCAUCACGGCGAUUAUCAUUAGCACUGGAUGAGAGAGAAACAGCACGUCCUUCCAGCGUCAGGCCUUGGAGUCAGACUAGGAAAGCACUAUUUUUAAAGUAGGAAUUUAAAGCUAGUAAAAAGUGUCACGGAGAAGAUUUCAGAUCCACUGUUUCUUUUACCUUUUGUGUUGGCCGAUUUGAAAAGCUUAGGAUGGAAAAGGCAGAAGUUAAGCCAAACUAGGAGACAAACUGCUGAGCCAUGAUUCAGCAGCUGGGACAUUUCCAGCCUGCACACCGUCCUCACCGGCUCCCAGCGAGGCACCCGGCUCUAGCCGCUCCAUUCAGCAGCGUGUGGACACCCCUGCUCAGUCCUUCGCCUGCCUGGCAUGUUCUUCGGGGCUCGUGCCCACCACCACUGACGCAAAAGAGGACCCUCUUGCCUGAAAUUAAUUAACUAAGGAUUCUCUCUUAAAGAUGAAAGAAAAUAAAACUUGGGGUUAAGAUGACAGACGGAGGGUCUCUCGGCACUUCACCCAUGUCGGCAUCUUGGAGCCAGCGUAGAAGCUUAUGAAGGAAUGGUUUCUCGCCUGCACACAGUCACGCAGGGCAUGUAGCAGCUCUCUACACACGUGCAUUUGCCUGUAAACUACAAAUGCUCACUGUCUUCAUUCCCAAGAGACUGAAGUGCCUGGAGAGGCUGGAUUAUUAUCCUCUCCCCCAGCUUUUCUUGCUCUGGGCAUCACUUGGGAUGGAUUGUACAGAAAACUGACCAUCUUAAUUAAAUGAGCAGGAGUUGUAAGGCUCUUCUAGAAUGGGAGGGCAAAGGUGGGAGUGUUUUUUCUCCCUGUAAUAGUCAAAUUUCCCCAGAAUGCCUAAAAAAACACGUGUUUCUCAUAGCGCUAUUUUGAUCUAGUAGUUCUUGCAAAAAGAGCUAGUGACAAAAUGAGAACUUUGAGAUCAGAAGAGCUGGGUACGAAUCCCAGCACUUUCGACGACACCUUGAUCAACAGCUGGGGACCUCUGACAUCCUUGAAUGUCAAAUCAUUCACCUGUAAAAUAUGAUUGCAACAAUCAUUGCCAAAAUAGAAUUCUAUAUCCAGCUGUUGUGAGGAUUGCAGCAUAAACUUAAACCUCCGUGAGACGAGCUGUCAUCACUAGUGCAGAUGUGAGGUCUGUCUCCUUGCCUGACGGGCACACUCCAUGCUGAUCCUAGAGAGAGCUGUGCCUUCCUGUGUGGAUACCUAACAGCAGUCCAUACUGUGACCACUGGCCCAGCAUCAAGGACGUGGAUGGCCACUCCCAGUUAUUAGUACCAACUGCUGUCUCCUUCAUGGACAUUUUGCCUGGGAUGGUUCUUUAUUGGAUUUUGGAGGAGCCAUACAAUUCUGGGUGUUUGUGGAGUCCUGGAGUCAUGGCCCACCUUCUGACACGAGAGCUGAAAUUUGGAAGCAUCAGAUUUCUGUGAUUUUAUUUAACCAGUAAUCUAAAAGCUCCUGCUGGAAAUGGAGAGUUUGCAUCCUGCUAAGGAAUAAUAUGCUGGAUGUCACCCAAUUCCAGAGCAUCAUCAAACAGUAGCUAGGAAUGUAUUCAGAUGCAAAAAGUAGAUGAUAGUGGCUUAAACAAAGUGGGGCUCACUGUUUUCACACAGUGAAUAUGAAGAUGGACCAUCCAGGGCUGGUGCUGUGACGAUGAUGAUGAUGGUGACAAUGACAAGGAUGACAAACUCUUACUGGGCAAGAAACUGCUCUGAGGGCUUGAUCUCAUUUACUACUUACUGCUAACCCACAAACUAGGUACUUUCCCUGUCUCCACAUCACAGAUGAGGAAACUGAGGCACAGAGCAUUCAGAUGACUUAACCCAAUUAGAAAUGGCAGAGCCAGAGCUGACACCACACUUUUUUCUCCUUUGUUAUUUUUGAAACAUGUUUAACAUUUAAAAUCUAUUAUUUGACACAUAUAAAAUAUUUCCCACAAUAUAUUUGUUGGUUAUACAAAGUAUAACAAUAGAACCUGUGAAGCCACCACCCGUCCAGUGACUAGGCUAUUACCAGUAUUACCUACGCGUUCCUUGCACCCUACCACCUGCCAGACACCUCCGGCUCCCGCAGGAAGCCACUGUCCGCGUGGCUUGCGUAUCUCCGGCGUAGAUGUGCUUAGACAACGUGUUGCUUAGCUUUGGUUUUGAGCACUGUGGGAAUGAUGUACUGUGUGGGGUAUUCUGAGACUUGCUUUUCUCCCCCCAGUUUAACAUCGUGUUUCUAAGGUUUAGCCACAGUGUGGCUAUGGCCCCAGCUUAGCUGUGGUUCUCUUACUUUCACUGCUGUGAACACUACCGUGUUUUUUGGCCAGCACAUCUCAAUGUAUCUGUCCAUUCUCCUGGCAUGUUUGUAAUUCUUUUUUAAGAAUUGUUGUUGGCCAGUCGUGGUGGCUCAUGCCUGUAAUUCCAGCACUUUGGGAGGCUGAGGCAGGUGGAUCACCUGAGGUCAGGAGAUCGAGACCAGCCUGGCCAACAUGGUGAAACCCUGUCUCUACUAAAAAUACAAAAAAUUAGCUGGGUGUGGUGGUGGGCACUCGUAGUCCCAGCUACUCGGGAGGCUGAGGCAGGAGAAUUGCUUGAACUGGGAGGCAGAGGUGGCAGUGAGCCGUGAUCGUGCCAUUGCACUCCAGCCUGGGCGACAGAGCGAGACUCUGUCUUGAAAAAAAAAAAAAAAGAAUUGUUGCUAAGAACAGCCUUAUACAAGACCGCUAGUACACAAAUGCCAGAGUUUCUUUGGGGUGUGUGCCUAGAAUUGGGAUUACUGGGUGUACAUAUACGGCAUAUGAAUCCUUUGUCAGUUAACAGGAGUGGGAAACCGUGUUUCCCAGUUUAUGAAUUUUUUUUACCUGUAUGGGGUGUCUUCUGAUUAAACUGGAGAGUUAACUUUUACAUAAUUGUAUAUAAAAAUUUAUUCUCUUUUAAUAACAAUUCUGUUAAGUUAUAAUUCACAUAGGAUGCACCUAUCUAGAGCAUGCAGCUCAGUGGGUUUUGGUACAUUCAGAGAGUUGUACAACUGUCCCCGCACCCCAUCUGAUAACAUUUUCAUCACCCCAGAAAGAAAUGCUAUCCCCGUCUUAGCAGUCAGUCCCCAUCUACCCCACUCCCUUAACCCUAAGCAGCCACUCAUCUACUCUCCGUCUCUCUAGAUUUGCCUAUUCUGGACAUUUCAUAUAAUGGAAUCAUACAGUAAUAAUAGGGUCUUUUUGUAUCUGGCUUCUUUGACUUAGCAUGUUUUCAAGGUUCAUCCAUUUUAUAACAUGUAUUAAUAUGUCAUGAUUUUUAUCACCAGAUAACAUUCCACUGUAAUGAAUUGCCCACAUUGUGUUUGCUCAUUUAUCAACCGAUGGACAUUUAGGUUGUUCCCAGGUUUUUUGCUGUUGUGAAUAACGCUGCUGUGGAUAUUCACGUGCAAGUUGUAUGUGGACGUAUGUUUUUACCUUUCUAGGGAGCUUAUCUAGCUGUGGAGUGGCUGAGUCAUAUGGCAGCUCUAUGUUUACAUUUCUGAGAAACUGCCAGGCUGUGGACCCACCCUUCACGGUCUCACCAGCCAUGUCUGAGGGUUCCAGUGUCACCACAUCCUCAUCAGCACUUGUGAUGAUGCGUCUUUUUUUCUGCACCCAUCUCAUAGAUGGAGUGGUUUGCAUUUCCCUUACGGCUAAUGACGUUGAACGUAUGUUCCUGUGCUUUUUGGUCAUUUGUGUCUCUUUUUUAGAGAACCGUCUGCUCAGAUUUUUGUUCAUGUUUAGUGGGUUUAUGUGGCUUUUAUUGUUGUAUAUUCUAGAUACGAGUCCUUUAUCAGACACGUGACUUGCAGUCAUUGUCAUCCUUCUCUGGGUUGUCUUUUCACUUUCUUGAUGGUGUCCUUUGGAGCACGGACAUUGUUUUUUUAAUCCACUCUGACAUUCUCUGUCUUUUGAUUGGUGUGUUGAGACCAUUCACAUUUAAAGUCCUUGCUGGCGUUGUUGGAUCAGUAUCUACCGUGUUUGUAACUUUUCUGUUUGUUACAUUUGUUCUCCGCACCCCUGCCCCUCCCCAACCCCACUCCUUUCUGCCUUCUCUGGUUUUCAUUGAGCCUUUUAGAUAAUUCCAUUUUGUCUCCUUGCUUAAUGUGUCGAUUAUACUUCUCUUAAAAUUUUUUUAGUGGUUUCCUUAAAGAUUACAAUACAGUUCAUACUUAACUGAUUUAAGUCCACCUUGAAGUAAUACCGUGCGGCAUCACGUGUAGUUCAGGUGCCUUAGAUCAUUACCAAUGUCCCCCUCACGGCCCCAUCUCUUAGGACACCAUUGUCUUCCUUCAGUUAGCGCUUCCUCUGUUCUUGUUUAAGAAAUCCUUCCUACCCCACAGUCAGAAAGAUCUCCUCUAGUGCUAGUCAGUGUCUCAGAAGGCAACAGGUGGCCCCUCUGUCCUCUUCUAAUAGCCCUCAUCCCGCCAGCUCAGAGCCAGAGUGGAGCCUCAGCCGUUCCUGGGUGUGUCCGCACACUCUGCUCUGGAGCUGGGGAAUGACCUCAGGAGGGGCUGAGCUGCACUGGACGUACCAUCAGAUGGUCCUGUUUCCAUGAGCAGAACAAGACGUGCUGUUUCCACCCAGCUCAGGACCUGUGCGUCUCAGUAGCACAUCAGGGCUGUAGAAUCAGUGCGGGUUUAGGGCCUGUGUUUAGUAGCCAGUGGGAGGUCAGCGUGUGUCCCUGUCCCCAGCACACAGCCGCCUGGCAACAAGUGGCCAUGCGAGUCUGGGGAACGUGUGAGGACAGGCUGAGGACAGGCUCACCACACACGCUGAUUGCCCCUCGCAGGGCCCUUUCUUAAAGGGUCCCAGCCUCCCCGUCAUUGGUCUGGACACUGGAUGAUGUUGCAAAUCCCCACUAUGGUUCUGCUCAGCAGACCCAGUAGGUCCCAGCUUCUGUGUGUCAAGCGGCAUCUGAUCAGGCUUGCCCUCUUUUUCAUCUUGGAGCCUCUCCCCAGGUCCUGCGAGUCAAGUACACUGAGUAGCCUCUGUCCCCUUGCUUAGGUGAUCACUCUGGUAUGCCCGCCGCUGGCCCCUACUACCCAGGAUCCCGCAGUUCCCGUGGAGAGUGGGAACCUGGUGCUGUGGGAGCAUCCCUUGUCACCGGCGGGAUAGAGCGGACAGCCUCCAUGGACUUCUUUAGGAGGACGCUGACCCUCCCCCAGGCAUUUUCCUAACCCCUUGGUGAGGAGACCAGCUCCAGGCCUCCCCAGGGAGUAUAGGCCAGGUGGCUUAACAGGGUGUCACGCAGUAGAUCCCUCCAGCCUCCCAUUUCCCUGCAUUCCCAGCAGACCAGCAGCAGCUACAUUUGGGACCUUGUUAGAAAUGAAAAUCCUUGGACCCCACCACAGCCUGCUCGAUCACAGACUCCGGGAGAGGGCCCAACAAUCUGGCUUUAAUAAACCGUCUGGGGCUGGAGAACCACAGCUCUGCAGGAUGUCCCGGAGGUCCAGCAUACUGACCUCAUCAGCGAUUGGUUUUUAUUAAUUCUAGACUUGGAUUAGCCAAUCUUGUAGACUAUACACACCCCUCGAUGUUCAAGGUUCACAUUAAAUGACCAAAUUGUGAGGGAACCACCUUGUCCACACGUGUGGGUACAUAUGACCUACUUGCAUUUCGUCCCGCUUGGAGCCCACCUCCCAGGCUCCUGCCCCCACACAGUGGACAUCUCCUUCUGACGCAGUUCCUGUGCCUUGGGGUCUGCCUUGUUUUAUGGGCCCAGGUGGCGCAGGAUGUGGGUGAGUCUGUGGAGAAAGGGCACCAGCUUGCAAGGCAGCAGCCCCAGGAGCAGCCUGGGAAGGCUUUGUGCAGAGGAGGCCUGUUUCCUCCUACGUGUUGGGAGAGUUGUCUCUGCAGAUGGUGGGUGAGAGUUCGCUGCCAAAACCACUGUCUUCCCUGCCCUGCGGACACUUCUUCCUCACCUUCCUAAAACUGUAAGAGACCUGGAGCCGUUGAGCAUCAAUGACUCUUUGACUCAGGAAUCUUAAAAAAUCACACCCUGGGGCUACCAUGGGGGCCUUCUGGUUCUCCUUGUGUAUUACUAGUUGAAUGUUUAUAGCUUUCAAUUUCUUUUUCCCCUUCUAUAUGCUCUCUAAGGACAUAGGAAGAAUCUACCUGACCUCACAGCUUUGGUAGGCACUGUUAUUGCCACACCCUCUUCUCCCAGUGGGCACCCCACACCCCAACUCCCCGGCACGUUGUUCAGUGGGACUGCCAGUAUCAUGUAUAAUCAUGAAUGCUGUGGAUUAUCCUUAUUCACACACACAGACUCACACCCUCACACCCAGAAAGGCAACUAUCCCAGUGCUCCCAGAAUAGAUGAACAACCGAAUCCCAGAUUCCCUUCGUGAGGAUUUAUUUGAAGACCACUUUCAGUAACAAUUACUUUAUCAGUGGAGGUCUCAGCAGGAAAGAUACGGCACAUAGUAGAGCACUUUGAGGAAGGUCACUAGACCGGUUCCCAAGGCAUGGGCGGAGUUCAGAGAAACCACCAGGAACUGGUAGCAGCAGAAUUGUUGCAACGCUUGGCCCCAAAGGAAGAGGGGAGGGAAUGUUGAUGGCACCUGGAAGGAGAGGUUGUAUUGACAAGUCUCCUUGGUAGAGCAGUGAUAUUCGGGGAGAAACACGGCCAGCCAGAAGUUACCCUGUAGAAGGGGGCAGAGGAGAAAACAAGCCAAUUCGACCCUCCUCCCAACCUGCCUCUCUCGUCUCUCCCAUUUUCUGUUUCCAAAACCGACCCACAGUCAGAGGGCAAAGGAGCCAACCAGAAGGCCCCUGUGUGUGAUUUUUAAGAUUCCUGAGUCAAAGAGUCAUUGAUGCUCAACGGCUCCAGGUCUCUUACAGUUUUAGGAAGGUGAGGAAGAAGUGUCCGCAGGGCAGGGAAGACAGUGGUUUUGGCAGCGAACUCUCACCCACCAUCUGCAGAGACAACUCUCCCAACACGGAGGAGGAAACGGCCCUCCUCUGCACAAAGCCUUCCCAGGCUGCUCCUGGGGCUGCUGCCUUGCAAGCUGGUGACCUUUCUCCACAGACUUGGGCCCCCAUAGCCAUGUGCCUGGGGCUGAAAGCACGGUAGAGGAAACCGGAAAGUGGAUUUAGAGGGACAAACAGAAGAUAUCCAACCCACUCUCAGACGUCCUCCUACAAGUUUUAGUUUUACUUCUCACACUUAAGUAUUUAAUCUAGCUCAAAUUGGUUUUGUGUUUGAUGUGAAGUAGGGAUUUUAUUUUAUUUUUUUCUCAUAUGAAUAACCACCUUUUCCCAGCAUCAUCAGUGGAUUAGUUCCUCCUUUCAACACUGAUAUUCUAUCAGUAAAUCAAGUUCUGUAUUUGCAUACAGAUUGUCUCCCUUUUCUGUUCCACGAGUUAAACUUGUCUGUCUCUGACCCAGUGCCUCACAGACUUCAGUACUGUAUCUUCAUAAUAAGGCUUGAUAUGUGGUGGGGCAAGUCUUAUUCUUUUUCAGGAGUUUUAGGCUAUUCUUGGCCCUUUGUUGUUUCAUAUUAACUUUGAAUCAACUUGACAAGUUCCACAAAACAAAAGCUGUUGGGAUUUUGACUGAAAUUUUAUUUAAUAUAUACAUCUAUCUAUCUAAUGUAUCUUUAUGAUAUGGGACCUUCCUAUCCAUGAGCAUGGUAUCUCUUUAUUUAGGUCUCCUUUAAGUAUUAGUAAAGUUUGUAAAUUCUUAUAUACACAACUUACACAUCUCUGAUAAAGGCAUAGGUACCUUAAGUGUCUAACAGUUGUUGCUAGUAUAUAGACGUGCAGUUGAUUUUUUAGAUUGGUCUCACAUCUAGCCACCUUUCAAUAAAGUCCCUUAUUUCUUCCAAUAAUUUGUCUAUUUUUUAUGUAAACCAUAGGAAACCAUAGAUUUGAUAUGGUUAUCUAUGUAGAUAGUCAUAUCAUCUGUGAAUAAUUGUAGUUUUGUCUCUCCCUAAUCAAUCUUUAAGCUAAUUAUUUAUUUAUCAUGGCUGUUGUUGACUAGAACUUUCAGUAUAAUGAUGAAUAAAAGCAUUGAUUUUGG